CUCUUUCCGUCUCAGGUCGCCGCUGCGAAGGGAGCCGCCGCCAUGUCUGCGCAUCUGCAAUGGAUGGUCGUGCGGAACUGCUCCAGUUUCCUGAUCAAGAGGAAUAAGCAGACCUACAGCACUGAGCCCAAUAACUUGAAGGCCCGCAAUUCCUUCCGCUACAACGGACUGAUUCACCGCAAGACUGUGGGCGUGGAGCCGGCAGCCGACGGCAAAGGUGUCGUGGUGGUCAUUAAGCGGAGAUCCGGCCAGCGGAAGCCUGCCACCUCCUAUGUGCGGACCACCAUCAACAAGAAUGCUCGCGCCACGCUCAGCAGCAUCAGACACAUGAUCCGCAAGAACAAGUACCGCCCCGACCUGCGCAUGGUGAGCUGGGGUUUGGGGAUCAGGCUUGGGGAGACUGGCCAGUGCUGUGGGGAAGGGCCUCCCACUACUGGUUGCAAUAUGGGCUGGAGAGGGAUGGAUUCUUGCUUUCAGCCUACUCCCCACACCCAGCAUUGGCCUAGGGGGCGGCUUGUGGAGUGUAUGGGCUGAGCCUUGCUCUGCUCCCCCGCCCCCAGGCAGCCAUCCGCAGGGCCAGCGCCAUCCUGCGCAGCCAGAAGCCUGUGAUGGUGAAGAGGAAGCGGACCCGCCCCACCAAGAGCUCCUGAGCCCCCUGCCCCCAGAGCAAUAAAGUCAGCUGGCUUUCUCACCUGCCUCGACUGGGCCUCCCUUUUUGAAACGCUCUGGGGAGCUCUGGCCCUGUGUGUUGUCAUUCAGGCCAUGUCAUCAAAACUCUGCAUGUCACCUUGUCCAUCUGGAGGUGAUGUCAAUGGCUGGCCAUGCAGGAGGGGUGGGGUAGCUGCCUUGUCCCUGGUGAGGGCAAGGGUCACUGUCUUCACAGAAAAAGUUUGCUGACUUGUGAUUGAGACCUACUGUCCCAUUGUGAGGUGGCCUGAAGAAUCCCAGCUGGGGCAGUGGCUUCCAUUCAGAAGAAGAAAGGCCUUUUCUAGCCCAGAAGGGUGCAGGCUGAGGGCUGGGCCCUGGGCCCUGGUGCUGUAGCACGGUUUGGGGACUUGGGGUGUUCCCAAGACCUGGGGGACGACAGACAUCACGGGAGGAAGAUGAGAUGACUUUUGCAUCCAGGGAGUGGGUGCAGCCACAUUUGGAGGGGAUGGGCUUUACUUGAUGCAACCUCAUCUCUGAGAUGGGCAACUUGGUGGGUGGUGGCUUAUAACUGUAAGGGAGAUGGCAGCCCCAGGGUACAGCCAGCAGGCAUUGAGCAGCCUUAGCAUUGUCCCCCUACUCCCGUCCUCCAGGUGUCCCCAUCCCUCCCCUGUCUCUUUGAGCUGGCUCUUGUCACUUAGGUCUCAUCUCAGUGGCCGCUCCUGGGCCACCCUGUCACCCAAGCUUUCCUGAUUGCCCAGCCCUCUUGUUUCCUUUGGCCUGUUUGCUCCCUAGUGUUUAUUACAGCUUGUGAGGCCAGGAGUUUGAGACCAUCCUAGGCAACAUAAUGAGACACCGUCUCUAAAAUAAAAUUAGCUGGGUGUGGUGGUGCACCGCCUGUGGUCCCAGCUCCUCAGAGGUUGAGUAGAGGCUGAGGUGAGCGGAGCACUUGAGCCAAGAGUAUGAGGCUGCAGUGAGCCCAUGAGCCCCACCACUACACUCCAGCCUGGAAGACACCAUGACACACAGUGAGGCCUGGAUGGGGAAAGAGUCCUGCUGUUGAUCCUCACAUGUUUCCUGGGCACCUAACUCUGUCAGCCACUGCCAGGGACCAAGGAUCCAGCAUCCAUGGCACCCCUGGUUCCUGCCAUCCUGGGGUACCCGAUUCAAAGAAGGACUCUGCUCCCUGUCUGAGACCACCCCCGGCUCUGACUGAGAGUAAGGGGACUGUCAGGGCCUCGACUUGCCAUUGGUUGGGGUCGUACGGGGCUGGGAGCCCUGCGUUUUGAGGCAGACCACUGCCCUUCCGACCUCAGUCCUGUCUGCUCCAGUCUUGCCCAGCUCGAAGGAGAGCAGAUCUGACCACUUGCCAGCCCCUGUCUGCUGUGAAUUACCAUUUCCUUUGUCCUUCCCUUAGUUGGGUCUAUUAGCUCAGAUUGAGAGGUGUUGCCUUAAAACUGAGUUGGGUGACUUGGUACCUGCUCAGGACCCCCCGCACUGUCCCAAUCCCACUCAGGCCCACCUCCAGCUGGCCUCACUCCGCUGGUGACUUCGUACCUGCUCAGGAGCCCCCACUGUCCCAGUCCCACUCAGGCCCAUCUCUGGCUGGCCUCACUGCGCUGGGACUCCGCCUUCAUAAGGAGAGCUCACUGCUCACGUUAGUAGAUGGCCCCUUCUCGUGAGGCCUCUCCCCUGGCACCUGCUUCAGUUGUCCUCCACAGCACUGAUUUGCAGCCCACAAGCUGGCAGGUUUAUCUGUCUCAUGUUUGUCUUGUGCUGGUGGGCAAGGGGUUUGUCUAGCACACCAGCAUAUAAUGAGAUGCUUGAUGAAUGGUGCAUAUUGAAUGUAUAAAGCCCACCGGUCCUGAGAGUUUGCUCACUGGAGACUUUCUGGAGAUGGAGUCUCGCUCUGUUGCCCAGGCUGGCGAGUGCAAUGGCGCGAUCUUGGCUCACUGCAGCCUCCACCUCCUGGGUUCAAGCGAUUCUCCUGCCUCAGCCUCCCGAGUAGCUGGGAUUACAGGUGGGUGUCACCACACCCAGCUCAGUAUUGUAUUUUUAGCAGAGAUGGGGUUUCACCAUUUUGCCCAGGCUGGUUUGGAACUCCUGACUUCAAAUUACCCACCUGCCUCAGCCUCCCAAAGUGCUGGCAUUACAGGCGCUCGAGGCUUUCUGAUGUGGCUGCUGCUGCUCAGAAGGCCUUGUCCUUAACCACCUCCUUGCCUGCCCUGGAGGCUUGUGCCUCUAGGCCCCACCCCCUGUGGAGUCCUGCUGGCUUUCUCCAUCCCUAUCUGAAUCCUCCCUGCUGUGUGGCCUCCCCUGGUCUCAUCCGUAACACAGCCCAGCUUAGUGGGCCUCUGUUCCUGCGGGUGGCCAGCCUGUCUGUGUGGCUGGGCUGGGGAGGCCACGUCUGGUAUCUGAAUGCUAUCGGUGGGUUGGGGUGGAGGAACCAGGAGAGGGCUGGAGGGAGGGAGAUGGUCUCAGCCCCACAGAGUUUGGAGUCCUCAGUGUGCUGAGCAAACGUGGAGACACCAUUUCCCUCCUCUAGACCUCAUCUUGGAGAGAGAGAUGUUGGAUGGGGCCAUCUAUUCCAGCUUUAUUCACACAAAUCAUGUCUGUUGGCCUGGAAAUUGGAAAACCAGUUAAACCAAAAACAUGAUAUUAAGAAAACAGGCAGGCUCACCAUAGUAAAAAUGCUGAAAGCCAAAGACAAAAUUGGGAGAACAAAAGAAAAGCGUCUUGUCACAUACAGAAGGUCCCUGAUAAAGUUAGUAGCUGCCCUCAUCAGAAACCAGGCCCAGGCAGUGGGGACACAUCCAGAGUGCUGAAAGAACCUCCCCCAGGUCAUCCUAUCCCCAAGAGUGAUGCCCGGCAGCAUUCCCAGCUCAGGGCUAAUGGUUCACGGAAGCCAGGAAUCAAACUGCCUGGGUUCCAGUCCCAGCUCUGCCAGUUAUGCCCAGCUGUGGGGACUUGGGCAGCUCGUUUAGUAGCACCGUGCCUCAGUUUCCCAUAUGUAAAAGGCCAUUUUGAGUGCCUUUCACAGCCCUGCAUAAGGCAGGUGUCUCAGUGUUCACUGCUGUCUCUCCAGCUCUUAGUCCAGUAGCUGCAUGGUGAGUGAGCGUAGGGCGCACCCUGGAAGGCUGCCAAGCCCAAAGUUGUGCAGAGCGCUGGGGACUCCAGACUCCCCACAGCAGCAGAGACUCGGGACUGAGGCAUCCUCUGUUCACAGGACAUGCUGGCAUCUACUGGGUCAGGGCUCUGCUGCUCGGUGGCUGUGCAACCUUGGGCAAGUUCCUCAACCUCUCUGUGUCUUCGUACCCUCAUCUGUAACAUGCGUGUCGAUAGACCCUACUACUCAGGGUUGAUGAGAAGAUUAAAUGUGCAAAACCUGCUUGACUGUGCCCACAAAUCCUGAUUGUAGGAAUAAAUUAAUGACUUUUUAUAAAUAUUUUGAUCAGAUGGACUCAUGAUCACAGAUGUCUUCACAUGCCUAUGACUAAUUUGUACACAAACUAAUGCUCGUGUUUCCCAAGCACCUGGAAGACAUGCCAGAUCCAUGUGCAGUAAUGCCUGGUGGCUCCAGGUCUGCCCCGCCGUCCUGUGGGGCUGUGAGCUUUCCCAGCCUCCUGCCCGUGUUUGUGAAUAUCAUUCUGUCCUCAGCUGCAUUUCCAGCCCAGGCUGUUUGGCGCUGCCCAGGAAUGGUAUCAAUUCCCCUGUUUCUCUUGUAGCCAGUUACUAGAAUAAAAUCAUCUACUUUAAAA